AGCUGCGGCGCGUGACGCGGGGCGCGCGGCUCCGUCGGCUACCGCGGGCGGGCGCAGGCGACGGGCACGGCGGGCGAGCGGGCGGUAUGGCGGCGGCGGGGCCCGCGGCGGGGCCGACGGGGCCCGAGCCCAUGCCGAGCUACGCGCAGCUAGUGCAGCGCGGCUGGGGCAGCGCGCUGGCGGCGGCGCGGGGCUGCACGGACUGCGGCUGGGGGCUGGCGCGUCGCGGCCUGGCUGAGCACGCGCACCUGGCGCCGCCCGAGCUGCUGCUGCUGGCGCUCGGCGCGCUGGGCUGGACCGCCCUGCGCUCCGCGGCCACUGCGCGCCUCUUUCGGCCCCUGGCGAAGCGGUGCUGCCUCCAGCCCAGAGAUGCCGCCAAGAUGCCCGAGAGCGCUUGGAAGUUUCUCUUCUACCUGGGCAGCUGGAGCUACAGUGCCUACCUGCUGUUUGGCACCGACUACCCCUUCUUCCAUGACCCACCAUCUGUCUUCUACGACUGGACGCCGGGCAUGGCAGUGCCACGGGACAUUGCAGCCGCCUACCUGCUCCAGGGAAGCUUCUAUGGCCACUCCAUCUACGCUACGCUAUACAUGGACACCUGGCGCAAGGACUCGGUGGUCAUGCUGCUCCACCACGUGGUCACUCUCAUCCUCAUCGUCUCCUCCUACGCCUUCCGGUACCACAAUGUGGGCAUCCUUGUGCUCUUCCUGCACGAUAUCAGUGACGUGCAGCUUGAGUUCACCAAGCUCAACAUUUACUUCAAGUCCCGCGGCGGCUCCUACCAUCGGCUGCAUGCCUUGGCAGCAGACUUGGGCUGCCUCAGCUUCGGCUUCAGCUGGUUCUGGUUCCGCCUCUACUGGUUCCCGCUCAAGGUCCUGUAUGCCACCAGUCACUGCAGUCUGCGCACGGUGCCUGACAUCCCCUUCUACUUCUUCUUCAAUGCGCUCCUGCUGCUGCUCACCCUUAUGAACCUCUACUGGUUCCUGUACAUCGUGGCGUUUGCAGCCAAGGUGUUGACAGGCCAGGUGCACGAGCUGAAGGACCUGCGGGAGUAUGACACAGCCGAGGCCCAGAGCCUGAAGCCCAGCAAAGCCGAGAAGCCACUGAGGAACGGCCUGGUGAAGGACAAGCGCUUCUGAACCCCUCGGCCCCGCCCCCGUGGACCCGGCCCCACCCCGAAUACCCCGGCCACGCUCCCCGUCCUUGGCCGCCCCUCCACCCCCUCCAACUCUGCUCCUCUAGGGCCGCCGCCACCUCCCCUGGGACCCCGCCCCCUCAUCCUGCCUCCAGUUCCCGGCCACGCCCCCCAGGACCCCUGCCCCUCCGGGGACACCGGCCCCGCCCUCAGCCCACUGGUCCCGGGCCGCCGCGGACCCUGCGCACUCUCUGGUCAUCGCCUGGGAGGAAGAUGCCACCGCCGCAGCAAGGUCCCUGCGGCCACCACCUCCUCCUCCUCCUGGCCCUGCUGCUGCCCUCGCUGCCCCUGACCCGCGCCCCCGUGCCCCCAGGCCCAGCCGCCGCCCUGCUCCAGGCUCUAGGACUGCGCGAUGAGCCCCAGGGUGCCCCCAGGCUCCGGCCGGUUCCCCCGGUCAUGUGGCGCCUGUUUCGACGCCGGGACCCCCAGGAGACCAGGUCUGGCUCGCGGCGGACGUCCCCAGGGGUCACCCUGCAACCGUGCCACGUGGAGGAGCUGGGGGUCGCCGGAAACAUCGUGCGCCACAUCCCGGACCGCGGUGCGCCCACCCGGGCCUCGGAGCCUGCCUCGGCCGCGGGGCAUUGCCCUGAGUGGACAGUCGUCUUCGACCUGUCGGCUGUGGAACCCGCUGAGCGCCCGAGCCGGGCCCGCCUGGAGCUGCGUUUCGCGGCGGCGGCGGCGGCAGCCCCGGAGGGCGGCUGGGAGCUGAGCGUGGCGCAAGCGGGCCAGGGCGCGGGCGCGGACCCCGGGCCGGUGCUGCUCCGCCAGUUGGUGCCCGCCCUGGGGCCGCCAGUGCGCGCGGAGCUGCUGGGCGCCGCUUGGGCUCGCAACGCCUCAUGGCCGCGCAGCCUCCGCCUGGCGCUGGCGCUACGCCCCCGGGCCCCUGCCGCCUGCGCGCGCCUGGCCGAGGCCUCGCUGCUGCUGGUGACCCUCGACCCGCGCCUGUGCCACCCCCUGGCCCGGCCGCGGCGCGACGCCGAACCCGUGUUGGGCGGCGGCCCCGGGGGCGCUUGUCGCGCGCGGCGGCUGUACGUGAGCUUCCGCGAGGUGGGCUGGCACCGCUGGGUCAUCGCGCCGCGCGGCUUCCUGGCCAACUACUGCCAGGGUCAGUGCGCGCUGCCCGUCGCGCUGUCGGGGUCCGGGGGGCCGCCGGCGCUCAACCACGCUGUGCUGCGCGCGCUCAUGCACGCGGCCGCCCCGGGAGCCGCCGACCUGCCCUGCUGCGUGCCCGCGCGCCUGUCGCCCAUCUCCGUGCUCUUCUUUGACAACAGCGACAACGUGGUGCUGCGGCAGUAUGAGGACAUGGUGGUGGACGAGUGCGGCUGCCGCUAACCCGGGGCGGGCAGGGACGCGGGCCCAACAAUAAAUGCCGCGUGGUCUGCUC